ACUAGCCCACGGCGGGCGGACGAGAGAGCUGCGAGCUAACGGGUCCGGACGACGGCGGCGGCGGCGGCGGCGGCGGCGACGGCUUUCUGCGCGGGCGGCGGCGGCGGCCGGAGCGGCGAGCAUGGCCCGCGCGGCGCCGGGCGCUGACUGAGGGUCGUGCUGCGGCAGCCUGGCGCCCGACAUGUGAAGGGGAACCUGCCAGGGGAUUACUGUGAGCUCACAGCAGGAUAGGCUGGCCCCGGGGGAGUGGGGAUGGGCAGAACCUGGGCCAGGAGUAUUAGGAAGGAGACCUGGACCCUGGUAGGGAGCUCAGCACAAGCUCGCCUGACCCAGAUGGUAUUGGACACAGUGCCCCGCUGAACAGCAGCUGUUCCCAGCGCCAGAGGACCCCACAGCCACAGUAGGAGCUUUGCGACCCCUACGCAACUGCAGCUGGGGCUGGGGCCACCAGGAGAAGGGACCAGCACCUCAGAUGGGAAGCAGAAGGGCAAGACCUACUGCGGAAAGGAUCUCGAUCUCUGCAGCGGAGUUUUCCCACACUCACAGAGCUUCCUGUUUUUGUCCUCUCAGGGUUGGGGUCUGGCUCCCCUCCUCUGGCAGAGGUUUUGGGCCAGGAGGUGGGACAACACUUGCAUGGAACCCAAGUCCCCUGAAGCCCCUGUGCUCUCUGUUGUGAUUGGAGUUCUAGGGCUUCCCCGCUGCCGGGAACGAGGGGCCGCCUCAUUGUCUGCUCAUGAACCACAAGGACCCCGACUGCUCCAGACUGGAUUAUUUCAAGCCGCCAAAGAGGGGGACCCCUAGAGCUGGCAGCCAGCAAUCCCAAGGGACUAGAGGGCUGCAAUGGACUGACCUCCCCCUCACCAGGGUGGCAGGAGAGGCAGAGCCUCUGUGGCCUAGCUAGUGACGGAGAGACCCGAUGAAGCCCUAAGCAGGGGCCCCGCCUGACUCAGGGACAGGACAGCCACUCCUGCCAACGUGUGUUCUCCCUACAUGAGGGAGGGCGUGGCAAGGGACCCCUGCCACUGUCCCCUGCUGCAGCACGUGCCCCUAUGCCCUUUGCAUGUGGUGCCAGAAUAGGCAGGCUACGCCGUGGCUGGCCCCUCAGCGGGCUGGGAAAAGAGUGGCCACGGUGACCGUCACCCGCCUGCCGGCACCAUGAAGUGCUCCCUGCGGGUGUGGUUCCUCUCCGUGGCCUUCCUGCUGGUGUUCAUCAUGUCCCUGCUCUUCACCUACUCGCACCACAGCAUGGCCACGCUCCCCUACCUGGACUCAGGGGCCCUGGAUGGGACGCACCGGGUGAAGCUGGUGCCCGGCUAUGCCGGCCUGCAGCGCCUCAGCAAGGAGAGGCUCUCGGGCAAGAGCUGUGCCUGUCGCCGCUGCAUGGGCGAUGCCGGUGCCUCCGACUGGUUUGACAGCCACUUUGACGGUAACAUUUCCCCCGUCUGGACCCGAGAGAACAUGGAUCUUCCACCGGACGUCCAGAGGUGGUGGAUGAUGCUGCAGCCCCAGUUCAAGUCACACAACACCAAUGAGGUGCUGGAGAAGCUGUUCCAGAUAGUGCCUGGCGAGAACCCCUACCGCUUCCGGGACCCCCACCAGUGCCGGCGCUGUGCCGUGGUGGGGAACUCGGGCAACCUGCGGGGCUCUGGCUAUGGGCAGGACGUGGACGGGCACAACUUCAUCAUGAGGAUGAAUCAGGCGCCAACCGUGGGCUUUGAGCAGGAUGUUGGCAGCCGAACCACCCACCAUUUCAUGUACCCUGAGAGUGCCAAGAACCUGCCCGCCAACGUCAGCUUCGUGCUGGUGCCCUUCAAGGUCCUGGACCUUCUGUGGAUCGCCAGCGCCUUGUCCACGGGGCAGAUCCGAUUCACCUACGCCCCAGUGAAGUCCUUCCUUCGAGUGGAUAAAGAAAAGGUCCAGAUCUACAACCCAGCCUUCUUCAAGUAUAUCCACGACAGGUGGACAGAGCAUCACGGGCGGUACCCUUCCACGGGGAUGCUGGUGCUUUUCUUUGCCCUGCAUGUGUGUGAUGAGGUGAACGUGUACGGGUUCGGGGCCGACAGCCGGGGCAACUGGCACCACUACUGGGAGAACAACCGGUACGCGGGCGAGUUCCGGAAGACUGGCGUGCACGACGCGGACUUCGAGGCCCACAUCAUCGACAUGCUGGCCAAGGCCAGCAAGAUCGAAGUCUACCGGGGCAACUGAGCCGGGCCUCGCCGCGACCCUUCCGGCCCAUCUAUCGGGCACCGGGGCUCCGGCCCGGGACCCAGGACCAGCAACCCGCGACCAAUCAUGCUGCAGCCCAGGGGCGUCUGCUGUGCCCCGCCAAUCACGAGACUGGGGGACCGGCCGGGCCUGGCACCAAUCUGCGCUGCGGUCGGGCGGAGCUUCUGUUUCUCCCAGCCAAUCAUGUGACUCAAGGAAAACUUCCGGCGCUGUGUCCAGUCUCCUCCAAUCAAUGGCCUUCGGGGGCGGGCCAGCGGCCGCUCAAUCCCCACUCCCUCAUGCUUUGGGUUAGGGUUUUCUUUCACGCUUUCUGAGGAGGAGAGCAUGGCGCGGGCCUCGGCGAAGCACUUCCGUCAGCCUCGGGCGGAGGAUCGUCUUAGUAGCUGGCCAGACCUGGAGGAGAGCGGGCGGUCUUUGCGGGCCUCAGGAGAUAGGUGGCCGCCCGGCCCCUUUCCCCGCCUGCCCGGAUAGGUGCGUGCAGACCCACCAAAGAAAAGCGGUCGCUGCGGGACCCCCAGUCCCACCUCGGCCGCGCUGUGGGAUGGCUGCGCCCCCAGGGCUUCCUGCGUCUCCAGGAAGCCGGGAGUGGCGCCCUCUGCGGGGUGGGGUGCUCCCGGGCCGAACUCCGGACAGGUGGAGGGGACAGGGCAGAGCUCGAGGAAGCCCUGUCCCCUUCAGUGCAAGGUGCUGUCACUCACGUGUGCCCUCGACCCUCCCGUUCACCCGCAGCCUUCUCAGCGCCUCUCCCUGGGCCGGAGGCCUCCUCACCAGCCUACCUGUUGCUCUGGAAAAAAAUCCCGUCCCCCGACUCCGUCCCUACCCCCAGUCUUCGGCCGGCUCUGGCCCCUGGGGAGGGGGCUGCACGGCGGAAGGAGGCUGGCUAUGGGCCCGGCUGCCCGCUGCAUGUACCUCCUCCUCCACCCAUCGCCUCUUGCCUGGGGGUAACUUUGCCUGGGGCUCAUUCUUUGGUUAAGCUGAAGCUGCCGUGGGUGGCCAAACCGCAGAUUCUUUGCAAAUUCUGAGCUGGCAGAGCUCGCAGCCGGGAGCCGGCCGGGGAAGAGGAGACUUGCGCGCCGCAAGCCGCCUGCCUCCACCCUGCUCUCCAUCUCCCGCUCUAGAAGGGCUGGGAAGCUCGCGGCCGGGGUUCCACCUGGAAGCUGCUUGCAUGGCUGAACCCAGCUUAGGUCCCUGACGGGGCUGCUGGUGGAAUUCUCCCCCUUCGAAGCUGGGGAGGUUUAGGAGGGGGAAGGCUUCUGUGAAGCUCUCAAACCACUAAUAGAGCCCCCUCCCCAACAGUGACGGCGCAGAUGCUCCCCCUUUUCUUAGUUGACACCACCAGGCAGCUUCCUGGCCGUUGGUAGGUUCCUGCAGCUGGCUGAGGGAACAGGGACCGGCAGGGGACUUUGUUAGGGGAGGGUUGGGAUGGGCAGUGGGCCCCUGAAAGUUAAUAUAUUGGAACCUAGCUCGAGUGUCGUUCUUUCCAAUUCCGAAAGUAGAAAGAGUAAAAAUAGGGGUGAUUGGGGUGGGGUUAGUAGAAUGCCUCUCUCAGGGCGCUCCCCCCUCCCCCACCGUUUUAGAGAGCUAGGCCUCAGCCAGUCUUGCCACUCCCAUCUCAGUGCUUCCUGAAGAGGCUGUUUUGAGUGUUGAUGAAAAGCAAUGCAAUUAUGCCAAACAGUAUUGAGCAGAAUAAUUUAUUUCUUUUUUUUCUUUUGCUUUAAAUCAUGAAUCCCGCCAGGUACGGUGGCUCACACCUGUCAUCCCAGCACUUUGGGAGGCCAAGGCGGGCGGAUUACUUAAUACUUAAGGUCAGGAGUUCGAGACCAGCCUGGCCAAUAUGGUGAAACCUCGUCUCUACCAAAAAAAAAAAAAAAUACAAAAAUUAGCCAGGCGCAGUGGUGCGCACCUGUAAUCCCAGCUACUUGGAAGGCUGAGGCAGGAGAAUCCCUUGAACCGAGGAGGCGAAGGUUGCAGUGAGCCGAGAUUGUGCCACUGCACUCCAGCCUGGGCGACAGAGCAAGACCCUGUCUCAAAAAAAUUAAAUCAUGAAUCCCCAUCCUGGAAGAGGUAGGUCCCAGCAUCCAGCCAGAUUUUCUGCAAUAGUAAUUUAAACACACUUUUUUAUUUCCUUCCCUUUCUGAAUUAAAAGGAACAAAAAACUGUCUAGUCCUUCAUUGUUCUGAAAUGGGCAUGAUGGAAGAAGGCGGGUCUGGUAGGAUAGCUGUGACUGAUAAUGGCUGAGAACGUUGGGGGAUAUGGGAGGGGCGAGAUGACUCCCAGAUACCCUCCCCCACCUAUACAGGAGGCACCUCAUUCCUGGACUCUGCGCUCCAAGACACUGAAAUCUGAGCGGGUACAAGCAUUUUGGUUAAAAAUCAGCUCGUUGUCGCCUCUUGAGUUUCCUCCAGGAGAGGAGUUCAUUGGAGAGGAUUCCUGGUAGCAGCUCCUCGCAGUGGCUGUCCUGUAACCACUUUGGCCUCUGUCAACAUGAUGUCUCCAGGUAUCCAUCAGGCUCCGAUACAUUUGGGUGGCCACAGGCUGGGCUGUCCCCACCUCUCAGGGAAGUGCAUCUAAGUCAGGUUUUCCCCUCUGGCACAGCCCUGCCUCCACAGCCCAAUUUCCACCAUGCCACAGGCAACCCGCAUUUUUAUUUAUUUAAUUUAUUUAUUUAUUGAGACAGAGUCUUGUUCUGUUACCCAGGCUGGAGUGCAAUGGCCCGAUGUCGGCUCAUCCCAACCUCCACCUCCUGGGUUCAAGCGAUUCUUCUGCCUCAGGAGAGUAGGGAGUAGCUGGGAUUACAGGCAUGCACCACCACUCCCGGAUAAUUUUAUAUUUUUAGUAGAGACGGGUUUUCUCCAUGUUGGUCAGGCUAGUCUUGAACUCCAGACCUCAGGUGAUCUGCCCGCCUCGGCCUCCCAAAGUGCUGGGAUUACAGGCGUGAGCCAGUGUGCCUGGCCGAUUUUUUUUUUUUGAGACUGAUUCUCACUCUCGCCCAGGCUGGAGUGCAGUGGUGGGAUCUCGGCUCAUUGCAAGCUCCGCCUCCCGGGUUCACGCCAUUCUCCUGCCUCAGUCUCCCGAGUAGCUGAGACUACAGGUGACCGCCACGAUGCCCGGCAGUUUUUUUGUAUUUUUAGUAGAGACGGGGUUUCACUGUUAGCCAGGAUGGUCUCCAUCUCCUGACCUCGUGAUCUCCCCGCCUCAGCCUCCCAAAGUGCUGGGAUUACAGGCGUGAGCCACCGCGCCUGGCUUUUUUUUUUUUUUUUUUUUGAGAUGGAGUCUUGCUCUGUCACCCAGGCUGGAGUGCAGUGGCGCGAUCUUGGCUCACUGCAACCUCCGCCUCCCAAGUUCACCCACCUCAACCUCCCGAGUAGCUGGAAUUACAGGGGUGUGCCACCACACCCAGCUAAUUUUUGUAUUUUUAGUAGAGACGGGGUUUCACCAUGUUGGCCAGGCUGGUCUCGAACUCCUGACCACAGGUCAUCCACCCCCUUUGGCCUCCCAAUGUUUGACCACACCCAGCCCAUAAUAGAUUUUUAAAACUCCUAUAAAUAUCAUUCUACUUCCCUUUAUUGCUAAAAUGGGAGCUUUUUCAUCCAGUUUUUUGGGUGUGUUCCAAAUAUUUUGUUAAAUUUCCCGUCUAUUGCUGUUAUUGUUUCCAUUUAUUUGCCCAUGUGAGUUGAUACCUUUUUCAUUCCUUUCCCAUAGCUUUAGUGACGUUGUGGGAAGGGAAGUUAGGUAAGUGAUGUUUCAUCUUGUACUUACUAGACACCUUUUUCUUCCUUGAUUUCCUGAGUUCCCUGCCUCCACAGGUGUGUUUCACUCCUGGUUGCUUAUAUUUUUUUAUUUUUGAGAUGGAGUUUUGCUCUGUUGACCAGGCUGGAGUGCAGUGGCAUGAUCUCGGCUCACUGCAACCUGUGCCUCCUGGGUUCAAGCGAUUCUCCUGCCUCAGCCACCCAAAUAGCUGGGAUUACAGAUGCGCACCACCAUGCCCAGCUAAUUUUUGUAUUUUUAGUAGAGACGGGGUUUCACCAUGUUGGCCAGGCUGGUCUUGAACUCCUGACCUCGUGAUCUGCCCACCUUGGCCUCCCAAGGUGCUGGCAUUACAGGUGUGAGCCACCGUGCCCGGCCUCUGGUUGCUUAUUUAACCCCUUUGUCACGAUGGAGGCUUUUCUCUUUUUUUUUUUUUUUUUUCAGAUGGAGUCUCUCUCCAUUGCCCAGGCUGGAAUGCAGUGGUGCUAUGUCCGCUCACUGCAAGCUCCGCCUCCCGGGUUCACACCAUUCUCCUGUCUCAGCCUCCUGAGUAGCUGGGAUUACAGGCAUGCACUACCACGCCCGGCUAAUUUUGUAUUUUUAGUAGAGACGGGGUUUCUCCAUGUUGGUCAGGCUGGUCUUGAACUCCUGACGUCAGGUGAUCCGCCUGCCUUGGCCUCCCAAAUGGUAGGAUUACAGGCGUGAGCCACCAGACCCUUUUUUUUUUUUUUUUUUUUUUUUUAAGAGACAGGGUCUCCUGUCGCCCAGACUGGUGCAGAGCUCACUGCAGCCUCAAAAACUCCUGGAUUCAAGUGAUCCUCCCACCUCAGCCUCCAGAGCAGCUAGAGCCUAGCUAAAAAAUUUUUUAAAAACAUUUUAUGGCCAGGCACGGUGGCUCAUGCCUAUAAUCCCAGCAUUUUGGGAGGCUGAGGCAGGUGAAUCACGAGGUCAGGAGUUCAAGACCAGCCUGGCCAAGAUGGUGAAACCCCGUCUCUACUAAAAAUACAAAAAAUUGGCCAGGCUUAGUGGCAGACGGCUGUGAUCCCAGCUACUCGGGAGACCGAGGCAGAGAAUUGCUUGAACCUGGGAGGUGGAAGUUGUGGUGAGCCGAGAUUGAGCCACUGCACUCCAGCCUGAGCGACAGAGUAAGACUCCGUCUCAAAAAAAAAAAAGUAUUUUACCCAUCCACAGGCAGCAGACAAGGAAGUACCUUCUGUGACUGUCUGGCAAGGUCAGAGGCAUCAGGGAAGGUAAAAUACUGAAACUAUAUUUUUAAAAAUAAAAGUAUUCCCUUUUGAGUGUGAAUUAGGAAUCAAUGCCCCUUCUCACUACUUUUGUGAAAAAAAUCACAGCUCCUGCAGCAAGUCUAUGCCUGGGUAACAACCAACCCACAAAAUCCAAGAGGAGGUCCCCCUCUCCCGCCUCUGUGAGGCUUGAGGAGCAGUAUGUAUCUGGGCCAGCCUGGUCCUCAGAGUGUGGAAUUAACACCUUUCCUCUAGCAACUGUUUGUGCUGCUGAGAACAGCACAGACUCUCUGGCAGCCUGGUUCUCUCCAGAGGGAAGCCUGUGAAGCAGAAGAAACAUAUGGCAUCUGCACUCAGGGCGCCCAGUUCCAUCCGGCCUUGCUAUAAAAUGACUUUGCCUUUCCUUUUUUAAAAUUACAAAAAUAAUUCAACCAAUACAUAAACAUAUGAAGUGAAUCACGGAGGGCCUUCCUGCGAUAUCUUUUUUUGCCUACCAUUUGUCAUGGAAUGGGUAAAGGGGACCACAGAGGGAAGAGACGCUGCCCCUUCGCAGGGCCAUGGCAGUCCCCUGGGCUGCGUCUCCACGGUGCUUCCUGUGAAACGCUGUUACCACGGGCACCGCACUGGAGACCAUGAAAGGGAAGAGUUUGACAUCUCAGCUGUCUUUGCUAUAAAUAGAAAUAAAUAAACCUUAACUAAG